AGAAGCGGGCCAGCGCCGCCGGGAAAGGAGGUCGCCGCCCGGGGUCGCCCGGGCUUGCGGGUCGCCGCGCUUCCUCUGCGGGCGCUGCGGGAGGCGAGGGCCGCCUCGGCGGAGGAAGCCGACCCCGGGGUCUCCGCCAGCCCGCCGGCGCCGCCUCCGAGCCGCCUCGGCCGUAGCCUCGGCCCGGGCGGGAGGCGGCGGCCGCCGGCGAGGCGAGGCGGCCCGCGCCCUGCCUGUCAGGCCACCGGCCCGGCCCGCGGGCUGCCCCCGAUGCGGAGGCGCUGUCGCCGGGGCCAUGCAGCAGGCGCCGCAGCCUUACGAGUUCUUCAGCGAGGAGAACAGUCCGAAAUGGCGGGGACUGUUGGUCUCGGCCCUGCGGAAGAUGGAGUCUCGCUUUUUUGCCAGGCUGGGGUGUAGUGGUGCAAUCUUGGCUCACUGCAACCUCCACCUCUCAGGUUCAAGUGAUUCUCCUGCCUCAGCCUCCCGAGUAGCUGGGACUACAGGCGUGUGCCACCACGCCCAGGUUCAGGAACAAGUGCAUCCCACUCUCUCAGCUAAUGAAGAGUCUCUCUAUUAUAUUGAAGAGCUGAUUUUUCAGCUGCUUAAUAAAUUAUGCAUGGCCCAGCCAAGGACUGUUCAAGAUGUAGAGGAGCGAGUUCAGAAGACCUUUCCUCACCCAAUUGAUAAAUGGGCCAUUGCUGAUGCACAAUCUGCUAUAGAAAAACGAAAACGAAGAAAUCCUCUUUUACUGCCUGUGGACAAAAUCCAUCCUUCGUUGAAGGAAGUAUUAGGGUACAAAGUGGACUACCAUGUAUCCCUAUAUAUUGUGGCUGUACUAGAGUAUAUCUCAGCUGAUAUUUUAAAAUUGGCUGGUAAUUAUGUUUUUAAUAUCCGGCAUUAUGAAAUAUCUCAGCAGGACAUUAAAGUGUCAAUGUGUGCGGAUAAGCCUCUGGUAACCACAUUCUACUCUGCCUCUAUGAGUUUGUUCCAGAUUCCACAUGUUUUGAUGGACAUGUUUGAUCAGGAUGACAUAGGUUUGGUUUCUCUCUGUGAAGAUGAACCUAGUUCUUCUGGUGAAUUAAACUACUAUGAUCUUGUCAGAACUGAAAUCGCAGAAGAAAGACAGUAUCUACGGGAAUUAAAUAUGAUCAUAAAAGUGUUUCGAGAAGCCUUUCUUUCUGAUAGAAAGCUGUUUAAACCUUCUGAUAUCGAAAAGAUUUUUAGUAACAUUUCAGAUAUACAUGAAUUGACUGUGAAACUUUUAGGUUUGAUUGAAGACACAGUUGAAAUGACUGAUGAAAGCAGUCCUCAUCCCUUAGCUGGCAGCUGUUUUGAAGAUUUGGCAGAAGAGCAAGCAUUUGAUCCUUAUGAAACAUUAUCACAGGACAUUCUUUCACCAGAGUUUCAUGAACAUUUCAAUAAAUUGAUGGCCAGACCUGCAGUUGCUCUACACUUUCAGUCCAUUGCUGAUGGUUUUAAAGAGGCAGUUCGUUAUGUCCUUCCACGUCUUAUGCUGGUGCCAGUGUAUCACUGUUGGCACUACUUUGAGUUACUAAAGCAAUUGAAAGCAUGUAGUGAAGAACAAGAAGACAGAGAAUGUUUGAACCAAGCUAUUACUGCUCUCAUGAAUCUCCAAGGUAGCAUGGACCGAAUUUACAAGCAGUAUUCACCUAGACGUCGACCUGGAGAUCCUGUUUGCCCUUUUUAUAGUCACCAAUUAAGAAGCAAACACCUGGCUAUCAAAAAAAUGAAUGAAAUUCAGAAAAAUAUCGAUGGAUGGGAAGGCAAAGAUAUUGGACAGUGUUGUAAUGAAUUCAUUAUGGAGGGACCAUUGACAAGAAUCGGUGCCAAACAUGAACGGCAUAUUUUUCUGUUUGAUGGCUUAAUGAUCAGUUGUAAACCUAAUCAUGGCCAGACUCGGCUUCCAGGUUACAGUAGUGCAGAAUACAGGUUAAAAGAAAAAUUUGUCAUGAGGAAAAUACAAAUUUGUGAUAAAGAAGAUACUUGUGAGCACAAGCAUGCAUUUGAAUUAGUAUCCAAAGAUGAGAACAGCAUAAUAUUUGCUGCUAAGUCUGCUGAAGAAAAAAACAACUGGAUGGCAGCCCUUAUUUCUCUUCAUUAUCGUAGUACUCUAGAUCGAAUGUUAGAUUCAGUAUUAUUGAAAGAAGAAAAUGAGCAACCACUGAGAUUACCAAGUCCUGAAGUAUAUCGUUUUGUAGUAAAAGACUCUGAGGAAAACAUUGUUUUUGAAGACAACUUGCAAAGUAGAAGUGGCAUCCCCAUUAUUAAAGGAGGAACUGUAGUGAAAUUAAUUGAAAGGUUAACAUAUCAUAUGUAUGCAGAUCCCAAUUUUGUUCGUACUUUUCUUACCACAUAUCGUUCAUUUUGUAAACCACAGGAAUUGCUGAGCUUACUGAUUGAACGGUUUGAAAUUCCAGAGCCAGAACCUACUGACGCAGACAAAUUGGCAAUAGAGAAAGGCGAGCAGCCAAUCAGUGCAGACCUUAAAAGAUUUCGCAAGGAAUAUGUCCAACCAGUACAACUUAGGAUCUUAAAUGUAUUUCGGCAUUGGGUUGAACAUCAUUUUUAUGACUUUGAAAGAGACUUGGAAUUGCUUGAAAGACUAGAAUCCUUCAUUUCAAGUGUAAGAGGGAAAGCUAUGAAAAAAUGGGUAGAGUCAAUUGCUAAGAUCAUCAGGAGGAAGAAGCAAGCUCAGGCAAACGGAGUAAGCCAUAAUAUUACCUUUGAAAGUCCACCUCCACCAAUUGAAUGGCAUAUCAGCAAACCAGGACAGUUUGAAACAUUUGAUCUCAUGACACUUCAUCCAAUAGAAAUUGCACGUCAGCUGACACUUUUGGAGUCUGAUCUUUACAGGAAAGUUCAACCGUCUGAACUUGUAGGGAGUGUGUGGACCAAAGAAGAUAAAGAAAUAAAUUCUCCAAAUUUAUUAAAAAUGAUUCGCCAUACCACAAAUCUCACCCUCUGGUUUGAAAAAUGCAUUGUGGAAGCAGAAAAUUUUGAAGAACGGGUGGCAGUACUAAGUAGAAUUAUAGAAAUUCUGCAAGUUUUUCAAGAUUUGAAUAAUUUCAAUGGCGUAUUGGAGAUAGUCAGUGCAGUAAAUUCAGUGUCAGUAUACAGACUAGACCAUACCUUUGAGGCACUGCAGGAAAGGAAAAGGAAAAUUUUGGACGAAGCUGUGGAAUUAAGUCAAGAUCACUUUAAAAAAUACCUAGUAAAACUUAAGUCAAUCAAUCCACCUUGUGUGCCUUUUUUUGGAAUAUAUUUAACAAAUAUUCUGAAGACCGAAGAAGGGAAUAAUGAUUUUUUAAAAAAGAAAGGGAAAGAUUUAAUCAAUUUCAGUAAGAGGAGGAAAGUAGCUGAAAUUACUGGAGAAAUUCAGCAGUAUCAGAAUCAGCCUUACUGUUUACGGAUAGAACCAGAUAUGAGGAGAUUCUUUGAAAACCUUAACCCCAUGGGAAGUGCAUCUGAAAAAGAGUUUACAGAUUAUUUGUUCAACAAGUCACUAGAAAUUGAACCUCGAAACUGCAAACAGCCACCUCGAUUUCCUAGGAAAUCAACUUUUUCCUUAAAAUCUCCUGGAAUAAGGCCUAACACAGGCCGACAUGGCUCUACCUCAGGUACUUUACGAGGUCACCCAACACCAUUAGAAAGAGAACCAUGUAAAAUAAGCUUUAGUCGGAUUGCUGAAACUGAGCUGGAAUCAACAGUGUCAGCACCAACCUCUCCAAAUACACCAUCUACUCCACCAGUAUCUGCUUCUUCAGACCUUAGUGUAUUUUUAGAUGUGGAUCUCAACAGCUCCUGUGGCAGCAAUAGCAUCUUUGCUCCAGUGCUUUUGCCACAUUCAAAGUCUUUCUUUAGUUCAUGUGGUAGUUUACAUAAACUAAGUGAAGAGCCCCUGAUUCCUCCUCCUCUUCCUCCUCGAAAAAAGUUUGAUCAUGAUGCUUCAAAUUCCAAGGGAAAUAUGAAAUCUGAUGAUGAUCCUCCUGCUAUUCCACCGAGACAGCCUCCUCCUCCAAAGGUAAAACCCAGAGUUCCUGUUCCUACUGGUGCAUUUGAUGGGCCUCUGCAUAGUCCACCUCCGCCACCACCAAGAGAUCCUCUUCCUGAUACCCCUCCACCAGUUCCCCUUCGGCCUCCAGAACACUUUAUAAACUGUCCAUUUAAUCUUCAGCCACCUCCACUGGGGCAUCUUCACAGAGAUUCAGACUGGCUCAGAGACAUUAGUACGUGUCCAAAUUCGCCAAGCACUCCUCCUAGCACACCCUCUCCAAGGGUACCGCGUCGAUGCUAUGUGCUCAGUUCUAGUCAGAAUAAUCUUGCUCAUCCUCCAGCUCCCCCUGUUCCACCAAGGCAGAAUUCAAGCCCUCAUCUGCCAAAACUGCCACCAAAGACUUACAAACGGGAGCUUUCGCACCCCCCAUUGUACAGACUGCCUUUGCUAGAAAAUGCAGAAACUCCCCAAUGACCUUAGCCAUAUGUAGUCAUUGACACUGGAAUGGUAUUUGUAAAGUUUUUUUUUUAAUUUAUUCAAAAAAAGACAUAGUAUUUUAGUACUUUUUACAAAUAAUGCUCUUACAAAAAUGCUACUGAUCAAAUAAGCUUUUAAGAAUUGGAAAAAUAAAAAUACAAAAGUCCUUCACCAUUAUCCUCAGGUGAUCAGUAGCAUUGCCUUGUCUUGGAUCCUCAGUGCUGCCAAAAGGCCAGUAUAAAGAAUUUAUAUUUGCACUGUAAACUCUGCAAAAAUAUGGUUUAAAGUGACAUGAUUGCACUGAAAAGGGAUAGUGCUUUUGUGAAAUUUUUCAAAUUUGAGUAAUAGAUGCCUUUUUAAGGCAGUGAAUUUACACAAAUAUGGGAGGGGUAUAUGGUGUUACUGAUUUUUAAACCUCUUUGACCAUCUUCUAGUUUUUACUUCUAGUUUUUACAUCUAGGAGAAUUGUGAAUAACACCAACUGUUCUUAAACUCUUUAAUGCCAUGUCUUAAAUGCCGGUAUUUGCUGCUGAAGACAAAAAUGAAAAGUAGGAUGAAAAUAAUAGAAUGGCACUGUAAGUGUUUAUUAUUUUGUCAAAAUGUAAACAAAGACUACAUAACCCAAUGAUGGAGGGAAAAAGGGCAUGUAUCUCAUUCAGAUGUGCCUUUUGUUUUUGCAGACUAUGACGUCUUUAGCUAAUGAAUUGCCUAUUGUUAUGGAAAACAGUUAAUAUGCCAUGUAUGUACAGUUUUGUUUAUAUUGUAUAUUUAAAGAUACUGCUAAUAACCUAUAUAAAUUUAAGUGACUUGAGGCCUAUAAUACAAUCUGCUACUUUACUAAUUCAUAAAUUCAAAAAAAAUUCUAUGGCAUAGGAACCAACUGCCUUGCCUUCAAGACCUAGUAACUUUCUCUAUAAAUCUCGUGUUAACUGAAAUUUUUUUUAAAUAUAUUUUUUAGAUUGGUAAUAUUUAAACCAGCAAAUACUUAAAGCUUUAUUAAACAUUUUAAUCAGAUAAGUGAGUAAAGCUUUUAUUUGCCAUUUGGAUGCCUUCGUUCAAAGUGAUAGAGUGUUUUGCUGAUAGUGCUGUAGCAGCAGUUGUAAAGUAGCCAAAAGCCACGUUGUUUAUUUACUGGUUUGUGGCCUUUUACUGUGCUUUGUAUCAGAGUUCUUAACAAGAUUAAUAAAUCACCCCAGUCUUAAUUUUUAAAA